CUUGUGGGCGGGUCCAAUCGGCUGGGAGCCUCGUGGAGGCUGAGAUUGCUUCACCUGUGGUAUCAGACAUCACAACAUGGGGCUCACCAAGCAGUACCUACGCUAUGUUGCUAGUGCGGUCUUUGGCGUUAUCGGCAGCCAAAAAGGUAAUAUUGUCUUUGUGACACUUCGUGGUGAGAAAGGACGUUAUGUGGCAGUACCAGCUUGUGAACACGUUUUCAUCUGGGACUUAAGGAAAGGAGAGAAGAUUCUUAUCCUUCAGGGGCUUAAACAAGAAGUUACUUGCUUAUGCCCCUCCCCAGAUGGGCUACACUUAGCUGUUGGGUAUGAGGAUGGGUCGAUCCGAAUCUUCAGUCUCCUGAGUGGGGAAGGAAAUGUGACCUUCAAUGGUCACAAAGCAGCUAUCACUACCUUGAAGUAUGAUCAGCUAGGAGGCAGACUGGCAUCUGGGUCCAAGGACACAGAUAUUAUUGUAUGGGAUGUGAUCAAUGAAAGUGGUCUGUACCGUCUAAAGGGGCACAAGGAUGCCAUCACACAAGCAUUGUUUCUACGAGAAAAGAACCUGCUAGUUACUAGUGGGAAAGAUACCAUGGUGAAAUGGUGGGACCUUGAUACUCAGCACUGCUUUAAAACAAUGGUUGGCCACCGGACUGAGGUAUGGGGGUUGGUUCUGUUGUCAGAAGAAAAGCGACUCAUCACUGGGGCCUCAGACAGUGAACUGAGGGUAUGGGACAUAGCUUAUCUGCAAGAGAUUGAAGACCCGGAAGAACCAGACCCCAAGAAAAUCAAAGGAUCUUCUCCUGGAAUACAAGAUACUCUUGAGGCAGAGGAUGGUGCCUUUGAGACGGAUGAAGCCCCUGAGGAUCGAAUCCUUUCAUGCAGAAAAGCUGGUUCCAUAAUGCGGGAAGGAAGAGACAGAGUUGUAAACCUUGCAGUCGACAAGACAGGCAGGAUUCUUGCUUGCCAUGGAACUGACUCUGUGCUAGAAUUGUUUUGUAUCCUUUCCAAAAAGGAAAUUCAGAAGAAAAUGGAUAAGAAGAUGAAGAAAGCUAGAAAGAAAGCAAAAUUACAUUCUAGCAAAGGAGAGGAGGAAGAUCCUGAGGUUAAUGUUGAAAUGAGUCUGCAAGAUGAAAUCCAGCGGGUGACUAAUAUAAAAACUUCUGCCAAAAUCAAGUCCUUUGACUUGAUUCAUUCACCUCACGGAGAGUUAAAGGCUGUCUUCCUGCUGCAGAACAACCUGGUGGAAUUGUAUUCACUGAAUCCAUCCUUGCCUACUCCUCAGCCUGUCAGGACAAGCAGAAUCACUAUUGGGGGUCAUCGCAGUGAUGUGCGGACUUUGUCAUUCAGCUCAGACAAUAUUGCUGUUCUUUCAGCUGCAGCUGAUUCCAUUAAAAUAUGGAACAGGUCUACACUGCAGUGUAUUCGCACAAUGACCUGUGAAUAUGCACUUUGCUCAUUCUUUGUACCUGGUGAUAGACAGGUAGUCAUAGGAACAAAGACAGGGAAGCUGCAGCUUUAUGACUUGGCUUCAGGGAAUCUGCUGGAGACAAUAGAUGCACAUGAUGGAGCUUUGUGGUCCAUGUCCCUCUCUCCAGAUCAGCGUGGCUUUGUGACAGGUGGUGCAGAUAAAUCUGUCAAAUUCUGGGAUUUUGAGUUAGUGAAAGAUGAAAAUAGUACCCAAAAGAGACUUUCUGUGAAGCAAACCCGAACUUUGCAACUAGAUGAAGAUGUUCUGUGUGUCAGUUACUCUCCCAAUCAAAAGCUAUUGGCUGUGUCUUUGCUGGACUGUACUGUGAAAAUUUUCUACGUUGAUACUUUAAAGUUUUUUCUGUCACUGUAUGGACACAAACUGCCUGUUAUAUGCAUGGACAUCUCUCAUGAUGGAGCACUCAUAGCAACUGGCUCCGCUGAUAGGAAUGUGAAAAUCUGGGGUUUGGACUUUGGGGACUGCCACAAGUCUCUCUUUGCACAUGAUGACAGUGUGAUGUACCUACAGUUUGUACCCAAGUCUCACCUCUUCUUCACUGCCGGAAAAGAUCAUAAGAUUAAACAGUGGGAUGCAGACAAAUUUGAACACAUACAGACUCUGGAGGGUCAUCACCAGGAAAUAUGGUGUUUGGCUGUAAGCCCCAGUGGAGACUAUGUUGUAUCAUCGUCCCAUGACAAAUCUCUGAGACUUUGGGAGAGAACAAGGGAGCCUCUUAUUCUUGAGGAAGAAAGGGAGAUGGAAAGAGAAGCAGAAUAUGAGGAGAGUGUGGCCAAAGAAGACCAACCAGCAGUUCCAGGAGAGACUCAAGGUGACAGUUACUUUACUGGAAAGAAAACUAUUGAAACAGUGAAAGCAGCUGAGAGGAUUAUGGAGGCUAUUGAGUUGUACCGAGAAGAAACUGCAAAAAUGAAGGAACACAAAGCCAUUUGUAAAGCUGCAGGGAAAGAGGUUCCACUUCCCAGCAACCCCAUCCUAAUGGCUUAUGGCAGUAUCUCACCUUCAGCUUAUGUAUUAGAGAUUUUUAAAGGGAUCAAGUCGAGUGAGCUGGAAGAAUCUCUACUUGUGCUGCCUUUCUCUUAUGUCCCAGACAUUCUUAAACUCUUUAACGAAUUCAUUCAGCUGGGCUCUGAUGUUGAACUUAUAUGCCGGUGCCUCUUCUUCCUCCUUAGGAUUCACUUUGGACAGAUCACUAGCAAUCAAAUGCUUGUGCCAGUGAUAGAAAAAUUAAGGGAAACAACUAUUUCAAAAGUCAGCCAAGUCCGGGAUGUUAUCGGCUUCAAUAUGGCUGGUCUUGAUUAUCUCAAGAGGGAAUGCGAGGCAAAAAGUGAAGUUAUGUUUUUUGCUGAUGCUACUAGCCACUUGGAAGAGAAGAAGAGGAAGAGGAAAAAGAGGGAGAAGUUGAUUCUAACGUUGACUUAGAACUGAAAUGUGGUAUCUUUUUUUUUUUCAACUUUUUCCUUUAAAGGACUCCUAAACUAAGCACAGAAGAGUUGGCGUCAUCUUAAAAAUACCAAAUAACAGAAGAUCGCAUUGCAGAUGAUAUCAGGAUGUGGUUUCCAGCUUUGCCUGAGGGAAUUCCAACAUGAGAUUAUGGGCUGGCUCCAUUUCUUGGACUUAAAAUGCAUUAUUAGUUUAAAAAUCUUUCUGUGCUCUCAAAGCUUGAGCCUUGCAGCUCAAGCUUGUUGUUCCCUUUAUAUUCUAGCAGGGAAUAAAUAAUUGUUUUAAUUAGGUAUUUGUUUCAUUGGAGUUGAAAUUAACAUUUCAAAAGUUUUUCGUAUUUUUUUAUGGCAGAUGAUUUGUCAUUUAUUUAUAUUAGGUUUUACUGCCUAUUGAGACAACCAGGUGCAUAAUUGAUUGCCCUUUGGCCAUAAAAAUGCAGUGUCAUGGAUCUUAGAGCUAAAAAGGACUGUAAAAAUUACCCAGAACAGCGUCCUCAGACUUAACCUUCUGCAAGUUAUGUCUGUAUAUAAGAAGAUUCUAAUUGCUAACUGUUUAUACUUUUCUGAAUAAAAUAGUUGUUUCUAAUUAAAAAGUAGCCAAGCUAAGAUGCCUGGCUGGGCUUCUGAGGAAUUAAUACACUCGUGUGUGUGUGUGUGUGUGUGUGUGUGUGUGUGUGUGUAUGUGUAUGUGUAUGUACACAUACAUAUAUAUAGUUGACACUUGAAAAAUGCAGGUGGUAGGGGCACUGACCCACCCCUACGCCCCGCACAGUCAAAAAUCUGCAUAUAACUUUUGAUUCCCCAAAGUCUUAAGUACUAGUAGCCUGUUAUUGACUGGGAGCCUGACUGAUGUAUUAUAUAUAUUGUAUACUGUAUUCUUAAAGUAAGCUAGAGAAAAGAAAAUGUUACUUAGAAAAUCAUAAGGAAGAGAAAAUAUAUUUACUGUGUUUAUCAAUACUAUAAGUGUAUGUCAUCUGUUUAUAAAAUGAAUUGUCUGUCUGGAUUGGCAGGCAACCACAGCCGCAGACCUCAAUCUGUGGUACUUAUCAAGCAUCAGCUUUUUCUUGUAAUGUCAUGACUUUUCUCUGCUUUUUGGGAGCACUGUGAUAUGCAGUUUACUGGGGCGAUGAGUUGUUCAUGCACAGGUGAUUAGUGUCACAGCAUUUUAAGUGCAUACGCACAACACUUGAGCUCACUGCAUAGCAACAGGAGGUGGCUGUGAAAUUAUUUCAGUAACAUACUGUGUAUUACAGUUCAUUUUAUGCAGCUAUGAUUUAAUACUGCAUCUUUACAUUAUUUUACAUUUCUCCCAAAACUGUGAAUUGCACCAUGUAUGAUCUGUAUUUGUGUGUGUUAAUGUUGAUAAUAGAUUUGCGUGUAUUUUAUGGCAGUAAAUGAUAAAAUAGUCUAGUAUCUACAUAUAUUUUGUGCAUUCAUGAUAUAACUACUUUUUUCCUAAUUUUUUUCAUCUGAAACUUUUCUCAUUGUUUCAGAUCUCCAAAAAUUUUUCCAAUAUAUUUAUUGAAAAUAUCUGGGCUGCGUGCAGUGGCUCACGCCUGUAAUCCCACCACUGUGGGAGGCCGAGGCAGGCGGAUCACAAGGUCAGGAGUUCCAGACCAGCCUGGCCAACAUGGUGAAACCUCAUCUCUACUAAAAAUACAAAAAACUAGCUGGGCGUGGUGGCAGGCGCUUGUAAUCCCAGCUACUCAGGAGGCUGAGACAGGAGAAUCACUUGAACCCGGCAGGCGGAGAUUGCAGUUAGCCAAGACAGUGCCACCAGCAUUCCAGCCUGGGCAACACAGUGAGACUCCAUCUCCAAAAUAAUAAUAGUAAAAAAAAAUCUGUAUAACAGUGGAGCCAAGUGGUUAAAACCCAUGUUCAACGGAUUGUCUACUGUAUAUCUUCAUGGUAAGGAUUUGGGGAAUGUUCUAGGAAAAGAUAUUGACAGAUACCUCUGGGUCUGGGCUUUUCUUUUGGGGAAGUUUAUAAAUGACUAAAUCAUACUUCUUGUUACAGGCCUGUUUAGAUGUUCUGUAUCUUCUUGAGACAGUUUUGCUUUUUAUCUUUUUUGUUGUUGUUAAUCCCAAAGAUUUAAAACUAUGGUUUCUGUCUGAAUUUGGUCAUUGCAACCAAGUUACUGUGUUGUGGGGCCACCAUUUUCUUCUAGGCUCAGAUAUGCAGUCCUUGUGGCUUGCCGAUUUGUGUCCCAAACCACAAGUCUUAAUGUUCUUGAGCAUAACACAAUCACUGAAGUGAGUAAGGGAUGCAGUGGUGUUAUUUGUUGGGCAGAAUAAAUAAGUGAAUUUUGGCAUAGAGUUUCUGAAGGCAUAACUAUGAAGGCAAGAGAAUAGGCAGGCAGGAUAAUGCAUUCUAGGUGCUUUCCAAGGAGUCAGUGUUGUUUAGGCAGCUAUUCCUGCCACCAGGGAGAGGAGUUAAUUCUUGAAAAAAAAUUUAAUUUUUUAUGAGAACAGAAGUUGAUUCAAUAUCCUUCUUAGAGUUGCUCAUCAGAACAUAAAUGUCACUUUCUAGUAACAUUUUUGAUGGUUUCCAAACCAAAACAAGUUCCAGGAGGGCAUUCGAGAUGUAUACAUCAUCAAUAAUUACUCUUAUGUUAAAAGUUGCUGUUUUCCCGUAGCUUUGCCACCAUUUAUAACUCAAAAGCCUGAUAGUGCUAGGGAAUGUAAAGAUGUUUCUGUCUGCUAAGUGUUAUACUAAUCGAAGAGAAGGAGAACUUUUAUGAUAAAGUGACAUGUACAGAACCUAGCCAAGUUACAAUUUUUGGUCAAAAUACUUGAAACUCUUUAACUCUAAAAGUUUAAGGUCAAUAGGUGCAUUAUAAAGUAAAUUUUAAGCCAGGCAAAUUUCUAGUCAUUAAGUCAGUAUUCAUUGCCUUAGUCAGCCAUUGGCUGUAUAUAAUCCUUAAUAUAAAAACCAUCUAAUGACUAAUAUCUCUUGCAUAUUGUGAAGUAAGUUACCUAUAGAAAUUCUGUAGUACCAUAAAGAAAAGCCUUUUGAGAUUGCAGUGAGCUGAGAUUGUGCCACUGCACUCCAGUCUGGGCAACAGAGCCAGACUCCAUUGAAAAAAAAAAAAAAGGCUCUUGAAUGAUGUAUUGGGAGUAAAACAUUUAGGCUUAUUUUUAAAAAUGUAUAUAUCCAUCCACUUAGAGAAAAUAUGCUUAAAAAUUUUGAAAUUCACUGGCUGGAAGCUAGGUGCUUUGUAUAUUUGGUAUUAAAUUGUUUCUCAAUGGCAAAUGUCAUAAAUUAUAUCUCAUUCUAAAGAUAUCUAGCAAAUCUCCAGCAGAGAUCUAGGACAGUGCCCAGGAAAGCAAUGGUAUCUGUUGGUAGGUACAGGACUGUAUAUAGGACUCUAUUCACUUAGCUGUAAAUGAUGAGCCUGCUCAAUGCAGCCUUUUCAGGCCAGAUUAGUCUUCAGAAAGAGAGGGAGGUUGUGAGCAGAAGCUUAAUGAAGAAACCACAUUGGCUUACAGUUACUGUCUGCAAUCCACCCCCAUUCCUCACAAUUUAAGCUCCUAAGUUUGAGAUGGGGCUAAGGUUCUUAAAGGUAGUAUCACCAUAUAUUCAAGUCCUUUCUCUUUAUUUCUGAGGUUUUUGGGAUCCAAGCAGCCCUGGUAUGUUUUUAGAACACAGUACACAUUGUGUAACAGUCACUGAGCCCAACUCUUACAUAGGGCCUGGCAGUGUUGCCCUUGUGUAUCCCUUCCCCUUGAGUAUGGGGUCGGACCUAGUGACUGGCUUCUAGUGAACAGAAUACAGUAAAUAUAAUGGGAUGUGUCUUCCAAGAUUAGGGUAUAAAGCACUGAAUUCUACCUUGCAUGAGCAUUACAUUUUAUAAUAUAUAUAAAGAAGCAACUAGUAUAGUUAUUUAAACAAAUAUUUUCUUUUUUUUUUUUUUUGAGACAGAGUCUCGCUCUGUCUCCCAGGCUGGAGUGCAGUGGCACGAUCUUGGCUCACUGCAAGCUCCGCUUCCUGGGUUCACGCCAUUCUCCUGCCUCAGCCUCCAGAGUAGCUGGGACUACAGGCACCCGCCACCACACUUGGCUGAUUUUUUCUAUUGUUUAGUAGAGACGGGGUUUCACCAAGUUAGCCAGGAUGGUCUCGAUCUCCUGACCUUGUGAUCCACCCACCUCGGCCUCCCAAAGUGCUGGGAUUACAGGUGUGAGCCACCGGGCCCGGCCUAAACAAAUAUUUUCAUUCAUUCAGGCCAGGUGGCUUAUAGGUUUCUGACUAUAAGAAGAGGGGAAGAAACCUGGGGUCUAAUACCUCAAAUUUGAAUGCUUGACAAUCAAAUUCCCAUUUAUUACUUACUGUACCUAAUGUGGAGAAACUUUACGAGACAUGAAGACUCCAAGUGUGGAGGAAUAAAUUGUAGAAGUUCUCUGGACCAUUGGAUUUUCUUUUCCCUGGGGAAAGUCUUUUGGUCGUUUAUCAUAAUUGCUGCUUGUUAAAACAGGUAAAAUACUUGUUAAGGGCUGUGCUUUUCAUGACUAAAUUAUUUGCAUAUAUAAACCUAAAUAACAUUUUAGAAUCAUAGAAUUUCUUCUCUGGCAACAUCAGUUCAAUUUUAGGUAACUGUCUAUCCAAUGCAAAUUCUGCAUGCUCAGGCUUGGGGGUUAGAGGAUGGAUAUGCCAAUGUCUAGAAUGUCUUCUGUUCUCCCUAGUGUACAUUUCUCUCCUAACUGUGACUGGCUUUCUAUAAGGAGCCAUCAGUAUGGUCAAGCCCCAAACCAUAUCUACAUCAGAUUUCAUGCUUUUUUUUUUUUUUUUUGGUGGGGAGAGGGACAGAUCAUUGUUGACACUGUAAGUAAGUAGAUAAAAGAUCUGAUAAGAUUUUUUGCCCUUUAUCUGUGUCUGACAGGUUCUCUCUAAUCUAUAAGCAGGGAAAUAGAAAAUUUAUUAUAAAUACAAAUGAUUUCAUUGCUAUGAUCAGCAGCAGUGACUCAGGUAUUUGCAUCUAAUAACCUGUGUGGAGAGGGUAAGGGCACUUGAUUUAGUUACCAGAGGAAAAAACUAGUUCUUUGGCUAGUUUCCUUCUGUCACAAUGGAAAAACCCUGUCAUUACUCAAAGGAAGAGAAAAAGGGAGGGGAGGAAGGUGAGAGGAAGGGAGAGAGACUUUCCCAGUGAGGACUUUCCUUUCCUAUUUUAUAUUUUGCUCCAUUGUACUUACUGCCAUCAUUGUUUAUGGUUUACUUACUUUAUGUAUUGUCUGUCCUCCCACUGGAAUGUAAGCUACAUAAAGGCAGGCGUUUCGGCAUCUUUGAAAGCAUAAAUGAACAAAUGAACUAAACUUCAUUUAUUGACAUCAGUGCUAUCUGACACAAGUUCCUUUAACUUUCUCCUUCACCUCGGAAUAUCUGAAUCAUCAGCUAUCUUCAGCUUCUCCCUUGCCAAGACUAACCCUUCAGCUCUGUUUUUUAUUAUUCUUUUGCCCUGUUUUGGAUAUUGCAGUUUCAAUCACUUCUACUCAUUCAUAUUUUUAAUAUAUAUCUUCUGCUCCACUCUCUUCAGCCUACAAACAUGUAGGUCUACAUUAAACUGAAAAUCCUUCCUAUAUUCUGUUGCAUCCUUGAGUAACAUAUUCUCUUGCUCUUUCCUUUAAUAAAUUUUCUUGAAAGAAUAUCCAUAACUAAUGUUUCUGCUUUCUUAAUACAGUCAUUCUUUACCUUUUGCAAUUUAGUUUUUAUCCCAACCAAAUUUAACACUUUAAAUCUGAAUUUUCUUUGACAUCUCAAUAGCAUCCGUCAAUUGUGUCCGUCUUUUCCUUGAAAUUCUUCCUAAGGCUUUUGAAGUAUUUCACCAUUUUCUAAUUGCUGCUUUUGUCUCCACUGGCUCUUCUUCCUCCUGCUCCCUAAACCGACUCCAGAUUUCUGUUCCUUGCCCAUACAUUCAGCCAUCACCUCUGUGUAAACGAUGCUUAAAAUUAUUAUAUCUCCAAUUCUGACUUCUCAGUUGAGAUCUAAUAUUACAUAUACAUGAUUCAUUACCUCAGCCCAAAACUUUGAAGUUGAACUCGAUGUCCUCUUUCUUCCAUCCAUCAAUGGCUUCUACCUCAGAUUUUGCAGUUUCCUUCCCCCACCAUGUCUUUCAUUCAUGUCCCUCUUUUAUGUUGACUGUUCCCCCACUCCCAGUUCUUGUCCUCACACAUGGCCCAUUCAGGUAGACUUCUAAUGGUACUUUUACACAUCCAGUUGUUCCCCUUUGACAUGUCCUGCACAAUAACCCUGGAUUCAUCUUAAUAAAGAUAUGCUGAUCAUGUCACCCACAGGGUCAGGAAUCUGCAGUGGUUCACUGCUGCUUAAAUAAUAAAAUUCAAGCCAAGGAUUUAAGAUCUUUCAUAACUUGACUCCAACCUACUUUCCCACUAUAUUCCUAAUACUCAAGCUUUUGGCAAGUUGAACUCCCUGCCAAUCAUCCCAAACACCUGGAGCUUUCCUGUUGCCAUGGUUUUGUUCAUUAUUUUUACUUAAAGUUCCCGUCAAUCAAGUUUUCACAUUCUAUAAGAUCCAGCUCAAAAAUCAAAUAAAUAGAGAACUGUAACACAAGCAGCACACAAUUCAUGCCACUGGAGAAAGUACAAAAUAGAAAUAAAAUGUGAAGACUUUAUUUCUGCUACAAAUUAUAUAAUACCUUUUAAGACAGAGUCCAAUUAUCCAUUUUUAUAUAUGAUAAACUAUUUUAUACAGUACCUUGGAGGUAAUAGGUUCUUGAUAUCUAUCUAAUAUCUGUUUGGCUGAAGACACUGAUAAGGAGGAAUGCAUGCAUAAUUCAGUGAAUACCCAACCUUUAUAAUAAUAAGGUAUUUCCUAUCCUUCCAUAAAAUUAUAAUUUUUUUGUGAUAGAUACUUGCUGUUUUAUUAUUCUGUCUGAUAUUCCGUAGAUAGCCAAUAACAUUUACAUUUAUUCAAUCUGAAGUUACUGCACAUAUACUAUGUGUCAGGUAUUUUUUUAGAUUUGGCUAGGUGCUUUCAAAGAUGAAUGAAGAUGCUCUUUGUCUUAAUAAAUUUAACUCUGAUUUUGAAGAUAGAAUUAAUAAAGUAGAGAUGCAUUUUGACUUCCA